GUUUCCGGAACCUCCGGGUGUCAUCCGCGGGGAAAGGUGGGGAAGGGUCCCGGGAACGUGGUGGGGCAGGGCCUCCGAGCGUGGUUGGACUUUGAAGGGGAUCGGCCGCCGUGAGUGUGGGGCCUGCAGCCUACUCUCCCCGAGUCCCCUGCCCGGCCUGCCUCGCUCGAGGCACCCGACGGCUUCUGUCUCCGCGGGCUGGCGCCUGACCAGCCAGGCCCAGCGGUUCCCCGCCUACUGCAUUUGAAAGAUCCCGAAAACCCUGGAUGAUUGUGCCUGGGGUUGGCAAGUUCGUCUUGAGUGCCUUCAAGAAGGGUUCCUCAAGCAGUUGUCGAUAGAGCCCUCCCUACUGUAUACGCCCCCUCCGCUCAUUCCUGCUACUUCCUUUCUCCUCCUCGUAUUUCCCCCUCGGUCCUUUACGCCGCCUUUCCCCCUCAUUUGCAGAUGCUGCAUCCCCUUUUUGGAAUUGCUCAACCAGGUGGUAACCGGCGCCGCUUCCUGGCCUUGGGAGGUGGUUCCUUUCUUAACCCACAAGAACCUCUCCCAAGAGAACUUGGUCCUGAUGUCUGACCAUGGAGAUGUGAGCCUCCCGCCCGAAGACCGGGUGAGGGCUCUCUCCCAGCUGGGUAGUGCGGUAGAGGUGAAUGAAGACAUUCCACCCCGUCGGUACUUCCGCUCUGGAGUUGAGAUUAUCCGAAUGGCAUCCAUUUACUCUGAGGAAGGCAACAUUGAACAUGCCUUCAUCCUCUAUAACAAGUAUAUCACGCUCUUUAUUGAGAAACUACCAAAACAUCGAGAUUACAAAUCUGCUGUCAUUCCUGAAAAGAAAGACACAGUAAAGGUGGGUCUUCACUUUCAUUGUUGCCCAUCUAAAAGCUUCAGAGCAGCACAGACUGACUUCAAGAUAAAAGUAGUAGUCUCUGCAUCUGAGUACCAGAUCCUGCAAUAGGAGAUAAGGCCAUUUCACCACAACAGUUCUGAAGUAGCAGAAAUUAAAGGAGAUUGCAUUUCCCAAAGCAGAAGAGCUGAAGGCAGAGCUGUUAAAACGAUAUACCAAAGAAUAUACAGAAUAUAAUGAAGAAAAGAAGAAGGAAGCAGAGGAAUUGGCCCGGAACAUGGCCAUCCAGCAAGAGCUGGAAAAGGAAAAACAGAGGGUAGCACAACAGAAGCAGCAGCAAUUGGAACAGGAACAGUUCCAUGCCUUCGAGGAGAUGAUCCGGAACCAGGAGCUAGAAAAAGAGCGACUGAAAAUUGUACAGGAGUUUGGGAAGGUAGACCCUGGCCUAGGUGGCCCGCUAGUGCCUGACUUGGAGAAGCCCUCCUUAGAUGUGUUCCCCACCUUAACAGUCUCAUCCAUACAGCCUUCAGACUGUCACACAACUGUAAGGCCAGCUAAGCCACCUGUGGUGGACAGGUCCUUGAAACCUGGAGCACUGAGCAACUCAGAAAGUAUUCCCACAAUCGAUGGAUUGCGCCAUGUGGUGGUGCCUGGGCGGCUGUGCCCACAGUUUCUCCAGUUAGCCAGUGCCAACACUGCCCGGGGAGUGGAGACAUGUGGAAUUCUCUGUGGAAAACUGAUGAGGAAUGAAUUUACCAUUACCCAUGUUCUCAUCCCCAAGCAAAGUGCUGGGUCUGAUUACUGCAACACAGAGAACGAAGAAGAACUUUUCCUCAUACAGGAUCAGCAGGGCCUCAUCACACUGGGCUGGAUUCAUACUCACCCCACACAGACCGCGUUUCUCUCCAGUGUCGACCUACACACUCACUGCUCUUACCAGAUGAUGUUGCCAGAGUCAGUAGCCAUUGUUUGCUCCCCCAAGUUCCAGGAAACUGGAUUCUUUAAACUAACUGACCAUGGACUAGAGGAGAUUUCUUCCUGUCGCCAGAAAGGAUUUCAUCCACACAGCAAGGAUCCACCUCUGUUCUGUCCUGUACUUCAAUAAGAGAUUUGAAGGCAAAGGAAAAGAGAAGCCACUUCAGAUAGAGCUGCAGCCACGUGACUGUUGUGGACAGAGCAGUGACCAUCACAGACCUUCGAUGAGCGUUUGAGUCCAACACCUUCCAAGAACAACAAAACCAUAUCAGUGUACUGUAGCCCCUUAAUUUAAGCUUUCUAGAAAGCUUUGGAAGUUUUUGUAGAUAGUAGAAAGGGGGGCAUCACCUGAGAAAGAGCUGAUUUUGUAUUUCAGGUUUGAAAAGAAAUAACUGAACAUAUUUUUUAGGCAAGUCAGAAAGAGAACAUGGUCACCCAAAAGCAACUGUAACUCAGAAAUUAAGUUACUCAGAAAUUAAGUAGCUCAGAAAUUAAGAAAGAAUGGUAUAAUGAACCCCCAUAUACCCUUCCUUCUGGAUUCACCAAUUGUUAACAUUUUUUUCCUCUCAGCUAUCCUUCUAAUUUCUCUCUAAUUUCAAUUUGUUUAUAUUUACCUCUGGGCUCAAUAAGGGCAUCUGUGCAGAAAUUUGGAAGCCAUUUAGAAAAUCUUUUGGAUUUUCCUGUGGUUUAUGGCAAUAUGAAUGGAGCUUAUUACUGGGGUGAGGGACAGCUUACUCCAUUUGACCAGAUUGUUUGGCUAACACAUCCCGAAGAAUGAUUUUGUCAGGAAUUAUUGUUAUUUAAUAAAUAUUUCAGGAUAUUUUUCCUCUACAAUAAAGUAACAAUUAACUUAUGUUUUUGUGCUUCAGAGUGAUCCAUUUGAUCAAGCAUUGUAUAAACAGGUUAAAAAAAAGGUAUGGUUGUUUUGGAAAGGUGAAGGAAAAAUGGAAUUUGAGAUAUACUGACACUGAUGGUGUGUCCCAGUUCACUUUUAAUUACUCCUUGUUUUUUAUCUGCCUGUUGCCAUCUUCCAGAGGUGUUGUGAAGUCAUCUCUGUUCUUUUGGUGCUGUCUCAAAUGGGUCAACCAUUCACUUCCUCCUUAUGCCCUCCAUGCUUUUGGCUGAGGAUAAUGAAGCCUUUGUUUGGAGUACCAGGUUACACUCCAAUAAAUGAUUACAUUUCCCAGCCACCCCACCCUACCAAUUUCAUUGUGUUGGCUGUUCUUUUCUGACUAAGGCAAUACCUAGGAAAACGCUUGAAGCAGCAAUUGUUACUGCAAUUUUCUGUGAGCUGAGCCUGGUGUUCUAGGUGGCCUAGAAAUAAUGGUGUCAUUUGUGACACCUCGAGUGAGGGCAGGAGAGUAAAUACUUUGGCUAGGAGAAGAGUGAUUUAUUCUUUAUCAGAAUUCUAGGUGGGGGAGGGAGAAUCUGUGAAUGCAUAAAGUUUUCUUCAUUUUUAAAUUUUGUCUCAGUCUUUAUUGCUUAGGUUAGUGGUCCUUGAACUUGUCCCCUGAAAGAGCCCAGUUCUCUAUAUUCUUUUUCUUCUCUUGGGUUCUUAAUUCCCCAUAUAGUGGAAAUUCCUUCUUUGCUGUUUUGGUAUGGGUGGGUCUGGGGGCCAGCUGGGCUUGGACAAGCCAUUUCCUGCUGCAGCCCAGAGCAGCCUGGCUGUUCCACCUUGCUCUAAACAGUCCUGAAAUUGCCCAGUCCUCUGCUUUUGGGAAAUCCAUCCCCUUCUUCCCAUUCUUUGUCUACCACUUAGCUUAGGGCUUUCUUACCUUUUAUUUCGACUGUAGCCGUUGGCUUUUACCAAGUCUCUUUGUUUUUAGCAUUUCUUCAUUCCAGUCUGUUCUGCACACUUUGAUCAGGAGAAGCUUCUCACAUUCCAGCCAUGUUCAUGUUUUCUCUCUUGCUCAAAAACCUGCAAUAGCUUCCCAUUGCUGAAAAUCUAAAUUUAGCUUUUAGUCAGAACUUUCCACUUAAAGUUCUUACCCCUGGCUAUAUAUUCAAAUAUCUAGGGAGCAAUUUAAAAAAUACUGAUGCCUGUGUUCUACCCCCCACCAAUUAAAGCUGAAUCUCUAGGGUGGAGCCUCAGAUGUUGUUUCUGCAUUUGUCUUUCAAGCUGCUAGAAUUCUCAAGUACAACCAGGGUUGACAACCACUGCAUUGGUCUUUGAUACCUAAGAAUUGUGAGCUCUCUUAUCCGUCUCUGCCCACCAAAGACAUUCAGCCAGGUCAACAACAUAUCAUACGUUGCAACCACAUUGAUCACAGACUGAUCACCAAACUGCUAUAUUUUCUUUUCUCUUCCUCUAGGCACAAGAUAUCUUAGUGGCUAGAUGGGUGCAGGAAAUCAGUCUGUAGAUCCCUCUUCAUAUCUGCUGCAGCCUAGCCACUGCAGAGGCACUCUGCAUAGGAUGGUCUAAGUGUCUCUGUCUUCAUCUUACCUCUGUGGAGGAGACGUGGAAUCAAGCCAGCCCACAAGCCCUGAGACUGGAUAGGCCGGAGAGAAAGAGGAGUAGCCAGAGCGGUCGGGAAAAGAGGAAAGGAAUACUGUGGGUAAAAGGGACAAAGACCACGCAACCUGAGGAAAGACAUUGUAUUGAAAGGGUAAUGACUAUUUGGCUAAAGGGACUGACUCCUGGGUUCCCGAGGCUCAAAGACCAGGAGACUUUUCCACUCUUGCAAGCUGCACAAGUACCAUACUUAGUGUUCUGGGCUGAGAGGGGAGACAAAAGCAUCGUCAGGUUGCCAAACAAUGUCCCAGUUGCCCUGGGAGGCACAAACCUACCAAAGUGCCAUAGGCCAGGUGCAGAGAGAAUCAGAGGAGCUGAUUUGCUUGGGGUCAGAGCAGAGCUGGGUUUUUUCAGAUGAUCACUUUCACAUACUCCUUGUUAAAUGGGACCAAAGGGGAAGAAGAAGAAACCCUUAAGCUUUUGUAAUAUUGUCUUGGGUACCAGAUACCAUAAAAGGCAGCAUGAGAGAAACAUUCCCUUGGGCCAGUGUCAUGGUGGAUUUUCUUGCUUGAGAGGCAAGGAUUUCAGCUUUCAUUUGGUACCACAGAAUUUAAAAUUGUAAGUGCCUAUCCCUUUUGACUGUUGAUGGCUUCUUUGGGGUUUUAGUUACCCCAGUUGAAAGAGAAAUUUUUCAUAUUGGGGUUGAGAAGAAUGGAGGCUAUUAGGAGCAAAGCUUUAAUGAGUGAAAGUCUGGUGAAUCCUGCAAUUUUGAUAUGUUUCCAGUGGAUUUUGAGAACACAGUUUUAGGACCAGAGUAGAUGUUGUUCCCUAGAAAAUAGAGUCAGCUAUUGAUAUUGUGCCUCCCAUCCCUCAUAUCUCAGUGUUUUAACCCCACCUGAGUUUGGAGACCAGUUUGUCCAAGGAUCUUUCAAACAUGUGAGCCCAGAGUAGAACUUCUGAGUCAAGGAUCAUGUCUUUUUCUGAGGAGCUUUGCUUGGGGCACUGGAAAUCCUGUUUAGAUCAGGACUAUUGGAAUAUUAUCCUCUCCAGGGGAAGUGCCAGGUUGAACAUUUAAGGCUUUGCUUCUAGGCCCAGCUAUACAUUCACCAGCAAAUCACUUAACUUCCUAAAUUUCUUUAAAAUCUGUAAAAUGGGAUCAGUCUAAUAUGCCUACCUCAAAUGAUGACAGAAUGACAUCUAUAUGCAUAUGAGGCCUACGUUAGUUGAAAGAUGCUAUAAAGAUAUAAGGGAUUUGUUACUUGUCUUUCUUGAAAUGUUACAGUUGGGGUGCGGUUGCUUCUAUCUUCUGGACCUCUGCCCAUUCAGCAUACAGCUAGAGGAAUCUUUGGGCAGAUCCACAUUCUUUAGCACUAGCUAGGCUUUGACUCCAAAGCUAUCUGGUCUACCUUGAUGUUCUGAGCAGGAAAACUGAGGACCUCAAGAACCAUUCCAAAUUUCUACUCAUUCUCCCUAAGACCCAGAGCAGACCCAGGACCUAAAGAAAUUACAUCAUCUCUAUUUUCCCUUGGCUCCAGCCCACUCUUGUUUGAACCUCCCACUUUUGUUGUUCCAACUACUUCUUGAGAUGAAGGAAGGGCAGAACAUUGGCCCUCUUCACUGAAGUCUUCACCCCUUAAUCCAGGGUUCAAUUUUUAGUUCACCUUAGCCUGUUUGAGAUUAGAAGCUGGGCCUUAACUUACAGGUGUGUCCGGCAUCAUUCAAUCAGCCUGUUAGAUCCAGAAUCCAGCACUGUGACGCUACAUAACCAUGGGCUCUGUCCUUCCAGUUCCUUUAGUGCCUUCCCUCACUGGUAGGUUCACUCUGAGGGCUUCCUUCCUUGAACUCCAGUGGCAACUAUAGUCUGUUUCCCACAAUUUGUUGUGUGUGUUUUUUGUUGUUUUGCAGCGUUUUCAUAUUGUCUUUUAUGUAAGUCAUGUUUCUGAACUAUCGUAUAAAUUUCAUUAGGGUAAGAAUCAUGUUUGCUUUAUGCACUGUGUAACAUGCCUUGCAGUCAGUAUAGGCACUUAACCUUAUUGAUCAGUUGUUCCUUGGUGUUGAAUAAUGUGUUAGGUAGCCAGGUGGACCUGUGUCCUAGCCUGGAGAAGCUCUAUGUCACCUUGUAGGAAGCCAUCUGAAUUUGACUCAGCAUCAUAUGCUGGGCCUGUGCUGCACUUGAGCUUUCUUUCCAGCCGCCAGGAGGGAUGGUUGUCCUGGCCAACAGCGAAUUUAAUGGGUGGUCAAAAGAAGAUGUGCCUGCAUAGAAGGCUGAAAGAGGGAGCUGGAAGUAGGAGGAGACAAGGAGAUAGUGACACCAGUAUCUUGUCACAGAAAUCAAGGAAGGCAACAGUUUAAAGGAGGGGAGGGAGAUCAGUGGUGCCAACUGGCUCAGAAGAGGUUUGCUGGGUUAAAUCUCAAGAUGAGCCCAUGAGAUCUGGUGGUUAGCAGAGGCCUUUCCUGACAACCCCAUUUUAAGCACCUCUUCCCCAUCACUCUAUCUCAUCACUGUUACUGUCUGUGUAGCCCUGUCAUGAGCUAAAAUCAUCCUGUUUGUUUAUUGCUAGCUUAUGUGUCUAAAGUAUACUCCUUGAGAACAGCAACUUUGUCUUUUUCACCUUUGUACUGAGUCCCCUGACAUGGAAUAAGAUAUGAAUAAAUGCACAGACUUGUCCAAAAUCAUCCAAUUAA